AUUUCGGGGCGACCCUCUUCUUGGCGUAGAGUUUUCAGAUUGCUCUUGGGAAUCAUGCCGAAAGUAGUGUCUCGGUCAGUAGUCUGCUCUGACACUCGGGACCGGGAGGAAUAUGACGACGGCGAGAAGCCCCUCCAUGUUUACUACUGUUUGUGCGGCCAGAUGGUCCUAGUGCUGGGUGAGUAGCCGGGAACUGCGGGGGCGUCUGCAAGGAGCCAGACUUCGGGUUCUUGAAGGCGAAUUUCCUCUGGCUGUGAUCUGGGAGCCACUUCUCAACGAAGAUUGACUGCCAGUUAGAGAAAUUGCCCAUGAGGCCCCGGGACCGGUCCCGUGUGAUUGAUGCUGCCAAACAUGCCCAUAAGUUUUGUAACACAGAAGAUGAGGAGACUAUGUAUCUGCGGUUUUUUUUCUUGAGAUGAAGUCUCACUCUGUUGCCCAGGCUGGAGUGCAGUGGCGCAAUCUUGGCUCACUGCAACCUCCACCUCCUGGGUUCAAGUGAUUCUCCUGCCUCAGCUUCCCGAGUAGCUGGGAUUACAGGCAUGCACCACCAUGCCUGGCUAAUUUUUGUAUUUUUAGUAGAGACGGGGUUUCACUGUGUUGGCCAGGCUGGUCUCGAACUCCUGACCUCAAAUGAUCCACCCGCCUUGGCCUCCCAAAGUGCUGGGAUUACAGGCGUGAGCCACCGUGCCCGGCC